GGAUCGAGGAUGAACUGGGAGGAGGAAGGUGGAGCCGUAGGAGAGGGAUUGAGGGCGGGGCUUGGAAACAAAUGACAGGGGAAGUCCAAGAGAGGGAACUCGAACCUUGAAAGCGGCCGAGAAGCUACAGGGGAGGGAGACCUGAGUUCUAAAUUAGGAACUCAAGGAUUAGAGUUUUGGAGAGGCGGGAGAGUGAGGACUGAGGGAGCCGAAAAGGGCGGUGACCGGAGUAUUCUAAGUAAAGUGUUUUGUAGAGAGGACUGUUGAGAGGAGAGUGUUAAAAAGAAGGAGCAUUUGGAGAACCGAAGUAAGAGGGGCAAUCCAGCGUGGCCUCUCCAGCCAUGCUUUUUGCAACUGCCUAACAUGUGGUGUUCUAUAAAUCCUCUUCCCCAGGUUUGCAGGAGGCCUAGGGAAGAGGGCAGAAACUAGGGAUGGAAAAGUGAGAUGGGCACAGCCUAGAGAGGAAGCAUUAAGGCUCUUGAAAGCAAUGCCCGCCAGGGAUGGCUGGCUGCCCUGCAGGACCGCAGCAUCCUUGCCCCCCUGGCAUGGGAUCUGGGGCUCCUGCUUCUAUUUGUUGGGCAGCACAGCCUCAUGGCAGCUGAAAGAGUGAAGGCAUGGACAUCCCGGUACUUUGGGGUCCUUCAGAGGUCACUGUAUGUGGCCUGCACUGCCCUGGCCUUGCAGGUAUGAGGCCCUGGCCUUGCAGCUGGUGAUGCGGUACUGGGAGCCCAUACCCAAAGGCCCUGUGUUGUGGGAGGCUCGGGCUGAGCCAUGGGCCACCUGGGUGCCGCUCCUCUGCUUUGUGCUCCAUGUCAUCUCCUGGCUCCUCAUCUUUAGCAUCCUUCUCGUCUUUGACUAUGCUGAGCUCAUGGGCCUCAAACAGGUAUACUACCAUGUGCUGGGGCUGGGCGAGCCUCUGGCCCUGAAGUCUCCCCGGGCUCUCAGACUCUUCUCCCACCUGCGCCACCCAGUGUGUGUGGAGCUGCUGACAGUGCUGUGGGUGGUGCCUACCCUGGGCACGGACCGUCUCCUCCUUGCUUUCCUCCUUACCCUCUACCUGGGCCUGGCUCACGGGCUUGAUCAGCAAGACCUCCGCUACCUCCGGGCCCAGCUACAAAGAAAACUCCACCUGCUCUCUCGGCCCCAGGAUGGGGAGGCAGAGUGAGGAGCUCACUCUGGUUACAAGCCCUGUUCUUCCUCUCCCACUGAAUUCUAAAUCCUUAACAUCCAGGCCCUGGCUGCUUCAUGCCAGAGGCCCAAAUCCAUGGACUGAAGGAGAUGCCCCUUCUACUACUUGAGACUUUAUUCUCUGGGUCCAGCUCCAUACCCUAAAUUCUGAGUUUCAGCCACUGAACUCCAAGGUCCACUUCUCACCAGCAAGGAAGAGUGGGGUAUGGAAGUCAUCUGUCCCUUCACUGUUUAGAGCAUGACACUCUCCCCCUCAACAGCCUCCUGAGAAGGAAAGGAUCUGCCCUGACCACUCCCCUGGCACUGUUACUUGCCUCUGCGCCUCAGGGGUCCCCUUCUGCACCGCUGGCUUCCACUCCAAGAAGGUGGACCAGGGUCUGCAAGUUCAACGGUCAUAGCUGUCCCUCCAGGCCCCAACCUUGCCUCACCACUCCCGGCCCUAGUCUCUGCACCUCCUUAGGCCCUGCCUCUGGGCUCAGACCCCAACCUAGUCAAGGGGAUUCUCCUGCUCUUAACUCGAUGACUUGGGGCUCCCUGCUCUCCCGAGGAAGAUGCUCUGCAGGAAAAUAAAAGUCAGCCUUUUUCUACA